GCCUUUUGCGCCAGCGUGAGCUCGGUUAGGGUCUCCACGGCCGUGCUUUCACCCCUCAGGGAGGCGUCGGUGAUUCGGUCACAGCCUCAGCCUCCGUCGCUCUGUGACCUGCGGGUAUUGGAUGAUUCGUAGCUGAGACUCCGCUACACCCCUGAAGUGGGGAAAUGGAACUCUUAACAUUCAGGGAUGUGGCCAUAGAAUUCUCUCCAGAAGAGUGGAAAUGCCUGGACCCUGCCCAGCAGAAUUUGUAUAGAGAUGUGAUGUUGGAGAACUACAGGAACCUGAUCUCCCUGGGUGUUGCUAUCUCUAACCCAGACCUGGUCAUCUAUCUGGAGCAAAGAAAGGAGCCCUACAAAGUGAAGAUACAUGAGACAGUAGCCAAACACCCAGCUGUGUGUUCUCAUUUCACCCAAGACUUUUUGCCAGUGCAGGGGAUAGAAGAUUCGUUCCACAAACUUAUAUUAAGAAGAUAUGAGAAAUGUGGACAUGAGAAUUUAGAAUUAAGAAAAAGCUGUAAAAGGAAGGUGCAGAAAGGAGGUUAUAAUGAAUUUAAUCAAUGCUUGUCAACUAUCCAGAGCAAAAUAUUUCAGUGUAAUGUACAUGUCAAAGUAUUUAGUACAUUUUCAAAUUCAAACCAACGUAGGAUAAGACAUACUGGAGAGAAACACUUUAAAGAAUGUGGCAAGUCAUUUCAGAAGUUCUCAGACCUAACUCAACAUCAAGGAAUUCAUGCUGGAGAGAAACCCUACACAUGUGAAGAAUGUGGCAAAGACUUUAAAUGGUAUUUAAUCUUUAAUGAAUAUGAGAUAAUUCAUACUGGAGAGAAACCCUUCACAUGUGAAGAAUGUGGCAACAUCUUUACCACAUCCUCAAACUUUGCUAAACAUAAAGUUCAUACUGGAGAGAAAUCUUACAAAUAUGAAGAAUGUGGCAAAGCCUUUAAUAGGUCCUCAACCCUUACUAAGCAUAAGAGAAUUCAUGCUGAAGAGAAACCCUUCACAUGUGAAGAAUGUGGCAAAAUCAUUACCUCAUCCUCAAAUGUUGCCAAACAUAAGAAAAUUCAUACCGGAGAGAAACUCUACAAAUGUCAGGAAUGUGGCAAAGUCUUUAAUAGGUCCACAACCCUUACUAAACAUAACAGAAUUCAUACUGGAGAGAAACCCUACACAUGUGAAGAAUGUGGCAAAGCCUUUAGUAGGUCCUCAGUUCUGAAUGAACAUAAGAGAAUUCAUACUGGAGAGAAGCCCUACAAAUGUGAACAAUGUGGCAAAGCCUUUAGACAAUCCGCAACCCUUAAUAAACAUAAGAGUAUUCAUACUGGAGAGAAACCCUACACAUGUGAAGAAUGUGGAAAAGCCUUUAGUCGGUUCACAACCCUUAAUGAACAUAAGAGAAUUCAUACUGGAGAGAGGCCCCACAAAUGUGAAGAGUGUGGCAAAGCCUUUGGAUGGUCCACAGACCUGAAUAAACAUAAGAUAAUUCAUACUGGAGAGAAACCUUACAAAUGUGAAGAGUGUGGCAAAGCCUUUGGAUGGUCUGCAUACCUGAGUAAACAUAAGAAAAUUCAUACUGGAGAGAAACCUUAUAGAUGUGAAGAGUGUGGCAAAGCCUUUUUAUGUUCCAGAGCCCUGAAUAAACAUAAGACAAUUCAUACUGGAGAGAAACCUUACGAAUGUGAAGAGUGUGGCAAAGCCUUUGGAUGGUCCACAUACCUGAGUAAACAUAAGAAAAUUCAUACUGGAGAGAAACCUUAUAGAUGUGAAGAGUGUGGCAAAGCAUUUAGACGUUCCAGAGUCCUGAAUAAAUAUAAGACAAUUCAUACUGGAGAUAAAACCCCCAAAUGUAAAGGAUGUGGCAAAGCCUUUAAGUGGUCCUCAUACCUUAAUCAACAUAAUAAAAUUUAUACUGGAGAGAAACUCUAGAAAUAUGAAGAAUGUGGCAAAGCCUUUGGAUGAUCCACAAACCUGAAUGAACAUAAGAAAAUUUAUACUGGAAAUAAACUAUACAAAUGUGAAGAAUGUGGCAAAGCUUUUGGAUGGUCCACAACCCUGAAUGAAAGUAAGAAUUCAUACUGGAGAAAAACCCUACAAAUGUAAAGAAUGUGGGAAAGCCUUCAAACAGUCCGCAUACCUGAAUCAACAUAAGAAAAUUGAUGCUGGAGAGCAACCCUACAAAUGUGAAGAAUGUGGCAAAGCUUUUAGAUGGUCCACAACCCUGAGUGAACAUAAGAAAAUUCAUAUGGGAGAUGAAUCCUACAAAUGUAAAGAAUGUGGGAAAGCCUAUAAACGGUCCUCACCCAUAAAUAAACAUGAGAAAAUUCAUAAUGGAGAGAACACCUACAAAUGU